CUGUCCCCGGCGAUUCCUGCGGACCCAGCUGCGGCGACGCCAGGAGACCCCAAGCUGCAUCGCCGAGUGGAAGCAACUAGAACUCCAGGGCUGUGAAAGCCACAGGUGGGGGCUGAGCGAGGCGUGGCCUCAGGAGCGGAGGACCCCCCCACUCUCCCUCGAGCGCCGCAGUCCACCGUAGCGGGUGGAGCCCGCCUUGGUGCGCAGUUGGAAAACCUCGGAGCCCCGCUGGAUCUCCUGGCUGCCACCCGCACCCCCCGCCAGCCUACGGUGCGCCCGCGGGCCCAGCUUCUCUCUGCGCUGCUCCCCGUUAAAUUCCCUGGGGAGACGGAAAAAAAGGCAAAGGAAGUCGGUUCUCCAGGGGCCAGAAGUGUUGAGCCUAAUUAGUCUUCAGACUUCUCAAUGAGGAAUCGCUUAUCAGUUUCUUAUCUGGGAGAGUUGAGGAUGGAGGGACAGAAGGCACCCAGGAUUUGCACGGGGGGGAUUCAGGGAGAGAGGGUGAUGAGGGACGGGGUGGGCCUUCCAGUCUUGGCCCAGUCCCCAUCUUGCACACAUUGUUGGCUUCCUCUUAGAGCCGUUCGCCCCCCUGGGGAGGGGAGACCCAUAGUGACCUCUCCUGACACCCGCCGACCCUGACCAGUGUUGCCGGGUUCUUCAAAGGCCACGCUCUGACUGCUGGUCUGUGUCACCUGCACCCCCCAGCCCCACCGUAGAGAUGCCUUCUUCGGUGACGGCGCUGGGUCAGGCCAGGUCCUCUGGCCCCGGGAUGGCCCCGAGCGCCUGCUGCUGCUCCCCUGCGGCCCUGCAGAGGAGGCUGCCCAUCCUGGCGUGGCUGCCCAGCUACUCCCUGCAGUGGCUGAAGAUGGAUUUCGUCGCCGGCCUCUCAGUUGGCCUCACUGCCAUUCCCCAGGCGCUGGCCUAUGCUGAAGUGGCUGGACUCCCGCCCCAGUAUGGCCUCUACUCUGCCUUCAUGGGCUGCUUCGUGUAUUUCUUCCUGGGCACCUCCCGGGAUGUGACUCUGGGCCCCACCGCCAUUAUGUCCCUCCUGGUCUCCUUCUACACCUUCCAUGAGCCCGCCUACGCUGUGCUGCUGGCCUUCCUGUCCGGCUGCAUCCAGCUGGCCAUGGGGGUCCUGCGUUUGGGGUUCCUGCUGGACUUCAUUUCCUACCCCGUCAUUAAAGGCUUCACCUCUGCUGCUGCCGUCACCAUCGGCUUUGGACAGAUCAAGAACCUGCUGGGACUACAGAACAUCCCCAGGCCGUUCUUCCUGCAGGUGUACCACACCUUCCUCAGGAUUGCAGAGACCAGGGUAGGUGACGCCGUCCUGGGGCUGGUCUGCAUGCUGCUGCUGCUGGUGCUGAAGCUGAUGCGGGACCACGUGCCUCCCGUCCACCCCGAGAUGCCCCCUGGUGUGCGGCUCAGCCGUGGGCUGGUCUGGGCUGCCACGACAGCUCGCAACGCCCUGGUGGUCUCCUUCGCAGCCCUGGUUGCGUACUCCUUCGAGGUGACUGGAUACCAGCCUUUCAUCCUAACAGGGGAGACAGCUGAGGGGCUCCCUCCAGUCCGGAUCCCGCCCUUCUCAGUGACCACAGCCAACGGGACGAUCUCCUUCACCGAGAUGGUGCAGGACAUGGGAGCCGGGCUGGCCGUGGUGCCCCUGAUGGGCCUCCUGGAGAGCAUUGCGGUGGCCAAAGCCUUCGCAUCUCAGAAUAAUUACCGCAUCGAUGCCAACCAGGAGCUGCUGGCCAUCGGUCUCACCAACAUGUUGGGCUCCCUCGUCUCCUCCUACCCGGUCACAGGCAGCUUUGGACGGACAGCCGUGAACGCUCAGUCGGGGGUGUGCACCCCGGCGGGGGGCCUGGUGACGGGAGUGCUGGUGCUGCUGUCUCUGGACUACCUGACCUCACUGUUCUACUACAUCCCCAAGUCUGCCCUGGCUGCCGUCAUCAUCAUGGCCGUGGCCCCGCUGUUCGACACCAAGAUCUUCAGGACGCUCUGGCGUGUUAAGAGGCUGGACCUGCUGCCCCUGUGCGUGACCUUCCUGCUGUGCUUCUGGGAGGUGCAGUACGGCAUCCUGGCCGGGGCCCUGGUGUCUCUGCUCAUGCUCCUGCACUCUGCAGCCAGGCCUGAGACCAAGGUGUCAGAGGGGCCGGUUCUGGUCCUGCAGCCGGCCAGCGGCCUGUCCUUCCCUGCCAUGGAGGCUCUGCGGGAGGAGAUCCUAAGCCGGGCCCUGGAAGUGUCCCCGCCACGCUGCCUGGUCCUGGAGUGCACCCAUGUCUGCAGCAUCGACUACACUGUGGUGCUGGGACUCGGCGAGCUCCUCCAGGACUUCCAGAAGCAGGGCGUCGCCCUGGCCUUUGUGGGCCUGCAGGUCCCCGUUCUCCGUGUCCUGCUGUCCGCUGACCUGAAGGGGUUCCAGUACUUCUCUACCCUGGAAGAAGCAGAGAAGCACCUGAGGCAGGAGCCAGGGACCCAGCCCUACAACAUCAGAGAAGACUCCAUUCUGGACCAAAAGGUUGCCCUGCUCAAGGCAUAAUGGGGCCACCCGUGGGCAUCCACAGUUUGCAGGGUGUUCCGGAAGGUUCUUGUCACUGUGAUUGGAUGCUGGAUGCCGCCUGAUAGACAUGCUGGCCUGGCUGAGAAACCCCUGAGCAGGUAACCCAGGGAAGAGAAGGAAGCCAGGCCUGGAGGUCCACGGCAGUGGGAGUGGGGCUCACUGGCUUCCUGUGGGAUGACUGGAAAAUGACCUCGCUGCUGUUCCCUGGCAUGACCCUCUUUGGAAGAGUGGUUUGGAGAGAGCCUUCUAGAAUGACAGACUGUGCGAGGAAGCAGGGGCAGGGGUUUCCAGCCCGGGCUGUGCGAGGCAUCCUGGGGCUGGCAGCACCUUCCCGGCUCACCAGUGCCACCUGCGGGGGAGGGACGGGGCAGGCAGGAGUCUGGGAGGCGGGUCCGCUCCUCUUGUCUGCGGCAUCUGUGCUCUCCGAGAGAAAACCAAGGUGUGUCAAAUGACGUCAAGUCUCUAUUUAAAAAUAAUUUUGUGUUUUCUAAAUGGAAAAAGUGAUAGCUUUGGUGAUUUUGUAAAAGUCAUAAAUGCUUAUUGUAAAAAAUACAGGAAACCACCCCUCACCCUGUCCACUUGGGUGAUCAUUCCAGACCCCUCCCCAAACAUGCAUAUGUACCUGUCCGUCAGUGUGUGGAUGUAUGUUUACAGUUCUACAUAAAUGGGAUCAUUUUAUACAUGGUGCUCUGGAACCCACAUUUUUCAUGCAGUCAUUUGCAGUGAAUUAUUUAUUGUGAUAAUAAAUAGCAUUAGAAUACAA